CCUCCCCCGGGGUCCUCCUCCGCGCCACCCCACCCCCGCGGCUCCUUUUUCUGCCUUUUCCUUUGUACCCUCACUGCUACCAGCUCCUUCUGGCGACCCCCAGGUACCCCCUCCCACCUUUCGUUUCUCUCUGGGUCAGCAGACCACGCAUGUAUCCAGAGGCGCUACCUGUAGGGAUCCUAAGCAACCCGGACACUUUCAAACGCCGUAGCGGUUCCUAUAGCAACGACAAACCGGAAGUAUGGUUUGCCGCCGGAAGCGGAAGUCCCAAUCAAAAGUUGAGCAGUAGCUGUGUGGGACGUGCGUGCGGCGAGAUGGACACUCCCCCGCUCUCGGAUUCGGAGUCGGAAUCCGAUGAAUCCCUUGUCACAGACAGAGAGUUGCAGGAUGCGUUUUCCCGAGGGCUUCUGAAGCCAGGCCUCAAUGUCGUGCUAGAGGGGCCGAAGAAGGCCGUGAACGACGUGAAUGGCCUGAAGCAAUGUUUGGCAGAAUUCAAGCGGGAUCUGGAAUGGGUUGAAAGGCUCGAUGUGACACUGGGUCCGGUACCGGAGAUCGGUGGAUCUGAGGCGCCAGCACCUCAGAACAAGGACCAGAAAGCUGUUGAUCCAGAAGACGACUUCCAGCGAGAGAUGAGUUUCUAUCGCCAAGCCCAGGCCGCAGUGCUUGCAGUCUUACCCCGCCUCCAUCAGCUCAAAGUCCCUACGAAGCGACCCACUGAUUAUUUUGCGGAAAUGGCCAAAUCUGAUCUGCAGAUGCAGAAGAUUCGACAGAAGCUGCAGACUAAACAGGCUGCCAUGGAGAGGUCUGAAAAAGCUAAGCAACUGCGAGCACUUAGGAAAUACGGGAAGAAGGUGCAAACGGAGGUUCUUCAGAAGAGGCAGCAGGAGAAAGCCCAUAUGAUGAAUGCUAUUAAGAAAUAUCAGAAAGGCUUCUCUGAUAAACUGGAUUUCCUUGAGGGAGAUCAGAAACCUCUGGCACAGCGCAAGAAGGCAGGAGCCAAAGGCCAGCAGAUGAGGAAGGGGCCCAGUGCUAAACGACGGUAUAAAAACCAGAAGUUUGGUUUUGGUGGAAAGAAGAAAGGCUCAAAGUGGAACACUCGGGAGAGCUAUGAUGAUGUAUCUAGCUUCCGGGCCAAGACAGCUCAUGGCAGAGGCCUCAAGAGGCCUGGCAAGAAAGGGUCAAAUAAGAGACCUGGAAAACGAACAAGAGAGAAGAUGAAGAACAGAACACACUAAAUAGCAUCUUUGAAUACAAAGAACCAAGAAAAAGGAAUGAAGACUCGCAAUUUCACGACACACUUUGAUCCCUUCUGUUGGUGUCAUGUUGUAAACAUUUCUUUCAAUAAACUAAAGAAAAAUUAUUAAAGGAACACAUACCUUUGGUUAAAUAGUCUAGACUAAAAGAUUGAGAAGUUACUUUCCAUUGCUAUCUAUUGAUAAUUUAGACAUUGAGUUCAAAUUGCCUUCAUUUUAUGAUAAAUAAUGAUUUAACUGACACCUUCUCA